AUGCACGUGCGCGCUCGCGUGCGGGAGACCCCUCCCUUCCACACCACUUCCUUUCGGGACAAACCGGUAACCUCCGGCCCUGGAAGGUUUUGUCUAGUGGGUUCCGGAUGGACUGGUGUUCCCAGCACCCCCCCGGCACGUGUCCACGCGUGUGGCCCCGGUUUACCAUGGAACCAUCUCUGCAAUGCAGCCCCUUCCACAUUGCCCCAGCCCCAUGGAGCUGGUGCUCCGGUGGCGCUGUGCAAUUGCCUGUUCCUGUGUGCCUCUGCUCCCCCGACACUAGGAGCCCUGGAGGGCAGGGCCAGAAUGCUUGUUAACCCUGUGAGGACAGCUUCACCAGAGGAGCCCUUGGGAGCUUAUACUGCCCAGGCCUGUCUCCACCAGGUUCAUGGAGCAAGUACAGCCCAGACUGGCUGAGGAGGAAGGAUUGUGGCCACACUACACCUAUUGGGUGUCAGUCAGUCCUCCAGAGAUCAAUUCUUCCAUUAGCAAUGCCACACAUAAUUCCUAAUUCUCCAAAUUCCAGUUCCCCAUCUAGCCAAACACACAGUCACUAACAUUACAUUGUGGUUCCACUUACAAAUGACUGCAUUUUCAGGUGGAGGUGUUCCCUUAAACCAUUUUCUCUGGAUGGCGUUCCUUCCUCCCUCUUCUUCUUCAUCCCCAUUUUCAGUCCGUAGGAUGAGCUUCUUUGUAUGUAAUCUCCCAAACGUCUACCGCUGGAGUUCUCAGCUUUGACCCCCAUCAGACUACACAUGAGGCAGGGUGCAGAUUCUUCCACUUUCACCUCCUCUCCCCUUCUCUCCCUCCGCCGCCUUUUUAAAAAAUGUUACUUGUCCCAUUUCUACAUUGUGAAAACACGUAGAGUUGCAUUCCAUUCCUCAGCCCUGAACCACACCUUUGUUUUUGUCUUGGAUCUGCAAUUGAAGAUAUUAAAAGCUGUUUGCCAUUC